GUAAGUAUCAUCCUAGAUACACCUUCUUGGGUUGUUAGUCAUUCCUGCAUUUAAAUUAGCAAGAUCUAGAAGAUUUUUGACCCUUCAGUGAGUCCUAAUAGUGCAUGUAUUAUAAGAGAGAAAGUGAAUGCAAAUGUACUGCCUCAUGGUUCAGUGUUUUAUUCUUUUGGAUAGGUGAUUAGAUGAUUUCACUUUUAUCUUUUUUUUUUUUUACCUCUAAACAGUCUAUUUUAUAAAUGCUGUUAUUGUGACCACUUUUUGCACUGGAAAGUACUUUGUUUUGGGGGGAUUGUUUUGAUCCAUACACUUUUAAAAUUGGUAAAAGCACCUCUGGUUUUUAUGACAAACAGUCCAUAUUUUUAAAAGAAGCAUCCCUACUUUAAAUAUUUAGUUUAAAAAAUAUACAUUGUAGUAGCACAGAUAAUUCAAAGAAUCAAAACUGUAAUCACCUUAAUUAUUCAUAUACUGAGUAUCUGAUUGGAGGAUUAGCUAAGAUUUUCUCAUUCCAUAUGUCAUCCAUUUCUUAAUUGCUUUUUUAUAAUUUUUUAAUUGUAUUUUAUCUAUACAUAUGUGUAUUUACUUAUACGACAGGAAAAUAAUGGAAAGACUUAAGUUGAUAUUUAAAAUUAAAGUGCUCAGAAACAUUUAUUUGAACCUACCAUGUGCCAGGGGAAGCUUUCAAAGCUAAAUAAGAUAUCUUUAAACAAUAGAAUUUCAUUAUGUUUUAUGUUUUGGUCUUAUUUAUGUUGUUAUUAAACUGAUGGUGGCUUGUAGCUAAAAAUCAGUUUUUUAAAAGCUUUUCUAUACUUCUAAGAUAGUGCUACAAGUAUGGUUUAGUCCUCUGGCCUCUAGGAUGAUUGAUUCCUUUUGAUUUUUUCUCCUACCUUUAUAUGGCUAUUAGGAAAUAACCAGCAAUAAAUUAUGGAAUCAGUCAAUGGAGAUACAAAGCAAGCAUCUAAGUAAAAGACCUUUUCUGGGUAGCGUAAGAUCAAGUCUCCUUUCUGCUACUGUUUUUCAUAGUCGGCUUCCUGAGUAUAUUUGAAAAGUUUUUUAGAUGUUUAGUACUACUUUUUUAAAUGGCCAUCUAGGUGUAUUAAAUGAGCUUUGGUUUGGAUGGCUAGUUUUGGUUUUUAUUUUUUAACCUUAUUUUGCUUUAAUUGGCAGUUCAAAGUAGAAAUGACAUACUGAAAAAAUCAUUGAAAAACUAACAUUUGUCUUUCAAUGACUGAUUUCCUAACUAAUUUUUAAAUACUCGCAUUUCUCUGACAAAAUAUACUAGGGAAAUAUUUGGUAGUCCCAAGUGAUAUGGACUAUUUUUUAUACCUUAUUUAUUAAAGUAUUUUUAUGAAAAUUUUUCCAUAUAUACAUUUAAUUUAGUUUUUAACAUAUUAAUUGAAUAUUGAGGAAGCUAAAUUUUGCUGUAUUAAAUCUUAUAUUUGAGUAUUCAGCAAAUAUAAUUGCUCAGCUAAAUCUUUAUGUCAUUAUUUAUUCACCUGCUGAUUUGCCACCACUCUCUUAAGUAUAUUAAUAGACAAAGUAAUGGAGUGAUUUGGAGGAUACUUCUGGGGAUGUGAACAAUAUCACAUUUCUAAAUGGAAUUCUCCAAAGGUAGUAUCCUCCACUGAUGAUACAUGGGUGGUAGUAGUGGUGGUGGUUCAGUGGGAAUUGGAAGUUGCAGCUAUGAAGCAGUAUGUGAGCAGGUUUAUAACACACAUGCGCUAAUAGGGCUUGCGGAAGAGAACUUAAAACUUUCUAGACUUUGCUGGAAUCUCUUGAGGGAAAUUACAGCAGGUGAAACUACCCAAGAUAGGGGUUCUAAGGAGGAUACUACCUUCGGAGAACUUUAGUUAGAGGUAAGUGAUUUCUCAUUAUUUUCUGAAUUUAAAUCUAUAACCUAACUCUUCUUAGUCCACAAAUAUCAUCAUACAGCAUCUAAAAUUGGUUAUAUGUCACUGCUUGCCAUUUUGUAUUUUGUUAACUGUGUAUGUUUCAAAAAGAAUUUGACAUGCUUUAAAAAGAAUUGGAAUUAUGGAUUGCAAAAAUCUGGUUAAAAGAGGUACCAUAAAAUCACUCAUUGAGAUUAUAUAAAAUUGGCCUGAAUUUUAACUGGACUCUCUUAAAAUUAUUAUUCUACCUUUUUUAGUGGACUGGUAUUUUUGUCUUAUUUAAUAUAUUAGAUAUAGACGUAGGCUGGGCAUAGUGGCUCACACCUGUAAUCCCAGCACUUUAGAAAGCCGAGGCGGGCAGAUCACUUGAGGACAGGAGUUCGAGACCAGUCUGACAAACAUGAUGAAACCUCGUCUCUACUAAAAAUUAGCUGGGCAUUGUGGUGCAUGCCUGUAUUCCCAGCUACUCGGGAGGCAGAGGCAGGAGAAUUGCUUGAACCCAGGAGGCAGAGGCUGCAAUGAGCUGAGAUCGCACCACUGCACUCCAGCCUGGGCAACUGAGCAUGACUCUGUCUCAAAAAAAACAAAAAAAGAUAUAGAUGUAGACAUAUACACUAGCACGUGCAUGUGCACGCACAUGUACACACUGAUGGUUAUAUAUUCUGUUUAUUGUAUGUUUUGUUUAGUGUGCCACAAUAUUAUGGGUUUAAUUUCAGAUAAUUAAGAGUGAGGUCUUUUAAAAAUUGAAGGGUUUUUCUUUUUUUUCUCUCUCUCUUUUAAAAAAUUUAUUAAAUAUUUAUUUCUUUUUUUAGAGAUGGGGUCUCGCUGUGUUGACCAGGCUGGUCUCAAACUCCUGGCCUCUAGCAAUCCUCCUGUCUCAGCCUCUCAAAGUGCUGGGAUUUCAGGCAUGAGCUACCACGCCCAGCCAGGGUUUUUCUUUUUUAAACCUUCAUCUAAAAUGUCCAAUUUCUGGAGUUGUUUUAUCUUUAUGGUCAAAUAAAUUAACUUGCAAAUAAUAGGUAGGAUUAAAAUAGGACUGAAAGUAGCACUCAUCUAACUUAUUAUAAUAUCCACAAUCAAUUUUUAUGGGUUUUUUUUUAGUAUGAUAACAGGUUAUUUUUAUAAUGAGUGCUGGGAGACUUCUGCAGUUUAAAAAAUAAGCUCCCGUAAAGUAGGGAGGUCAAAAAAAGCCUUUUAUUAUAAUAAUUUCUUUUUUCAAUAGAUUUUUAGUUAUUGUAACUGAUAUUUGUUAGAUUUCUGAUCUUCAUUUUACUCAUCCAAGUACGGAAUCAAUAUUGAAAGGCUCUUCUGCCAUUCUGUAUAUCUCAGAUUGAGUUCUGUUCAAUACUAGUCUGUAAAAGGAUUUAGUAGAUAUUUUGGGGAAGGUGUCCUUGAUUAAAUAGAUUUGGGAAACUAUAACAAUAAUCCUCUUUGGAAAUAUCACAGUGCAUAUUAUAUUUUAAAUGCCCCAGUGAUUCCUGUAGUUGAGAAGUUUGUUUAAAUGUGUUUAACCUAGCAUUUUCUUUCUCUGUGGGACAUCUGUUAAUAUCUCAAGAGACAUUAGGAUUCUGAGGAACAUAAUAUGGGAAGCUCUACAUUAGAUUAAGGAAGAAGCAUUGCAUGCAUUUAUUCAGCCAGAGAUUCUGGAUGGCCCAAAUCAGUAUUUUUGUGAACGUUGUAAGAAGAAGUGUGAUGCACGGAAGGGCCUUCGGUUUUUGCAUUUUCCUUAUCUGCUGACCUUACAGCUGAAAAGAUUCGAUUUUGAUUAUACAACCAUGCAUAGGAUUAAACUGAAUGAUCGAAUGACAUUUCCCGAGGAACUAGAUAUGAGUACUUUUAUUGAUGUUGAAGAUGAGAAAUCUCCUCAGACUGAAAGUUGCACUGACAGUGGAGCAGAAAAUGAAGGUAGUUGUCACAGUGAUCAGAUGAGCAACGAUUUCUCCAAUGAUGAUGGUGUUGAUGAAGGAAUCUGUCUUGAAACCAAUAGUGGAACUGAAAAGAUCUCAAAAUCUGGACUUGAAAAGAAUUCCUUGAUCUAUGAACUUUUCUCUGUUAUGGUUCAUUCUGGGAGCGCUGCUGGUGGUCAUUAUUAUGCAUGUAUAAAGUCAUUCAGUGAUGAGCAGUGGUACAGCUUCAAUGAUCAACAUGUCAGCAGGAUAACACAAGAGGACAUUAAGAAAACACAUGGUGGAUCUUCAGGAAGCAGAGGAUAUUAUUCUAGUGCUUUCGCAAGUUCCACAAAUGCAUAUAUGCUGAUCUAUAGACUGAAGGAUCCAGCCAGAAAUGCAAAAUUUCUAGAAGUGGAUGAAUACCCAGAACAUAUUAAAAACUUGGUGCAGAAAGAGAGAGAGUUGGAAGAACAAGAAAAGAGACAACGAGAAAUUGAGCGCAAUACAUGCAAGAUAAAAUUAUUCUGUUUGCAUCCUACAAAACAAGUAAUGAUGGAAAAUAAAUUGGAGGUUCAUAAGGAUAAGACAUUAAAGGAAGCAGUAGAAAUGGCUUAUAAGAUGAUGGAUUUAGAAGAGGUAAUACCCCUGGAUUGCUGUCGCCUUGUUAAAUAUGAUGAGUUUCAUGAUUAUCUAGAACGGUCAUAUGAAGGAGAAGAAGAUACACCAAUGGGGCUUCUACUAGGUGGCGUCAAGUCAACAUAUAUGUUUGAUCUGCUGUUGGAGACGAGAAAGCCUGAUCAGGUUUUCCAAUCUUAUAAACCUGGAGAAGUGAUGGUGAAAGUUCAUGUUGUUGAUCUAAAGGCAGAAUCUGUAGCUGCUCCUAUAACUGUUCGUGCUUACUUAAAUCAGACAGUUACAGAAUUCAAACAACUGAUUUCAAAGGCCAUCCAUUUACCUGCUGAAACAAUGAGAAUAGUGCUGGAACGCUGCUACAAUGAUUUGCGUCUUCUCAGUGUCUCCAGUAAAACCCUGAAAGCUGAAGGAUUUUUUAGAAGUAACAAGGUGUUUGUUGAAAGCUCCGAGACUUUGGAUUACCAGAUGGCCUUUGCAGACUCUCAUUUAUGGAAACUCCUGGAUCGGCAUGCAAAUACAAUCAGAUUAUUUGUUUUGCUACCUGAACAAUCCCCAGUAUCUUAUUCCAAAAGGACAGCAUACCAGAAAGCUGGAGGCGAUUCUGGUAAUGUGGAUGAUGACUGUGAAAGAGUCAAAGGACCUGUAGGAAGCCUAAAGUCUGUGGAAGCUAUUCUAGAAGAAAGCACUGAAAAACUCAAAAGCUUGUCACUGCAGCAACAGCAGGAUGGAGAUAAUGGGGACAGCAGCAAAAGUACUGAGACAAGUGACUUUGAAAACAUCGAAUCACCUCUCAAUGAGAGGGACUCUUCAGCAUCAGUGGAUAAUAGAGAACUUGAACAGCAUAUUCAGACUUCUGAUCCAGAAAAUUUUCAGUCUGAAGAACGAUCAGACUCAGAUGUGAAUAAUGACAGGAGUACAAGUUCAGUGGACAGUGAUAUUCUUAGCUCCAGUCAUAGCAGUGAUACUUUGUGCAAUGCAGACAAUGCUCAGAUCCCUUUGGCUAAUGGACUUGACUCUCACAGUAUCACAAGUAGUAGAAGAACGAAAGCAAAUGAAGGGAAAAAAGAAACAUGGGAUACAGCAGAAGAAGACUCUGGAACUGAUAGUGAAUAUGAUGAGAGUGGCAAGAGUAGGGGAGAAAUGCAGUACAUGUAUUUCAAAGCUGAACCUUAUGCUGCAGAUGAAGGUUCUGGGGAAGGACAUAAAUGGUUGAUGGUGCAUGUUGAUAAAAGAAUUACUCUGGCAGCUUUCAAACAACAUUUAGAGCCCUUUGUUGGAGUUUUGUCCUCUCACUUCAAGGUCUUUCGAGUGUAUGCCAGCAAUCAAGAGUUUGAGAGCGUCCGGCUGAAUGAGACACUUUCAUCAUUUUCUGAUGACAAUAAGAUUACAAUUAGACUGGGGAGAGCACUUAAAAAAGGAGAAUACAGAGUUAAAGUAUACCAGCUUUUGGUCAAUGAACAAGAGCCAUGCAAGUUUCUGCUAGAUGCUGUGUUUGCUAAAGGAAUGACUGUACGGCAAUCAAAAGAGGAAUUAAUUCCUCAGCUCAGGGAGCAAUGUGGUUUAGAGCUCAGUAUUGACAGGUUUCGUCUAAGGAAAAAAACAUGGAAGAAUCCUGGCACUGUCUUUUUGGAUUAUCAUAUUUAUGAAGAAGAUAUUAAUAUUUCCAGCAACUGGGAGGUUUUCCUUGAAGUUCUUGAUGGGGUAGAGAAGAUGAAGUCCAUGUCACAGCUUGCAGUUUUGUCAAGACGGUGGAAGCCUUCAGAGAUGAAGUUGGAUCCCUUCCAGGAGGUUGUAUUGGAAAGCAGUAGUGUGGACGAAUUGCGAGAGAAGCUUAGUGAAAUCAGUGGGAUUCCUUUGGAUGAUAUUGAAUUUGCUAAGGGUAGAGGAACAUUUCCCUGUGAUAUUUCUGUCCUUGAUAUUCAUCAGGAUUUAGACUGGAAUCCUAAAGUUUCUACCCUGAAUGUCUGGCCUCUUUAUAUCUGUGAUGAUGGUGCGGUCAUAUUUUAUAGGGAUAAAACAGAAGAAUUAAUGGAAUUGACAGAUGAGCAAAGAAAUGAACUGAUGAAAAAAGAAAGCAGUCGACUCCAGAAGACUGGACAUCGUGUAACAUACUCACCUCGUAAAGAGAAAGCACUAAAAAUAUAUCUGGAUGGAGCACCAAAUAAAGAUCUGACUCAAGACUGACUCUGAUAGUGUAGCAUUUUCCCUGGGGGAGUUUUGGUUUUAAUUAGAUGGUUCACUACCACUGGGUAGUGCCAUUUUGGCCGGACAUGGUUGGGGUAACCCAGUGACACCAGCACUGAUUGGACUGCCCUACACCAAUCAGAAGCUCAGUGCCCAAUGGGCCACUGUUUUGACUCGGAAUCAUGUUGUGCACUAUAGUCAAAUGUACUGUAAAGUGAAAAGGGAUGUGCAAAAAAAUAAAAAAAAACAACAAAAAAAGCUAACCUUCUAUUAGAAAAGGGGACAGGGGAAUGAGUAAACUUCUUUUAUUGCGGACAAAUGUGCACAUAGCCGCUAGUAAAACUAGCCUCAAACAGGAUGCUCAUAGCUUAAUAAUAAAAGCUGUGCAAAGGCCAUGAAUGAAUGAAUUUUCUGUUUAUUUCACUGAUGCACACAUUACCUCAUUGACAAUUCAGAAGUAAAUCCAACGUGUGUUGACUCUUGGAAAGCAGCAAAAACAGGAGCUGAAGAAAAGAAAUUCUUGGAACCAGCCGUAACCCAGUAAGGAAUUGUGAAGUUGUGUUUUUAUUUUGUUUCAUUUUUUGCAGAGUAUUAAGAACAUUAUUCUGGAACAUCAGAACGUUUCCCUUAGACCGAUCCCAGCAGGUGGCAGCUCAGAUUGCUGCAGUGUUGUAAUUAUAACUGAUUGUACUUAAGUUAUGGAUGUAGAGAAUAUGUUUCAUUCAUUUAUUCAGCAUGUAAAUAAAAUUGAUCCUGUUGAGUUAUCAUAAUUGCAGUUCAACUAUCUGCCAUGAUUAUUCUUUUCACGUAUCAUUCAUUCUGUACAUUUGUGUACAUUGAGAAGUAUAGCAAUCUAUGUAAAUGUAAUCCUCAGUGAGGUUCCUCAGUGCUAGGUCCCAUAGGAUUGUCGUUGCCCUUGUUAAUGAGGUUUCUCUGUUCAGCGGCUUCAAUUUUUUUCUCUUUGUACAUCUAGUUUUGAAGAUUUACUUCAAGUUUGAAUCUUCUAGAAUGCUUGUAAGUCCAGUUUUAAUUUUUAGAGUCAAUUUGUAGUUACAUGUAGUUUAACUUUUGGGAAACGUCUUAACAUUGUUCUGAAUAAACUUGCUAAUGAGGUCAGGUCAUGGUACAGACUGAUGCAGUCAACAUGAUUUCAUUGCAGAGUUUAUUAGUAUCAGCAAGUUUUUGCUUUGCUAAAUAAAAGUACUCAAUGAACACAAUUCUACAUAAAUUUUGACAUACCAUCUAAUUUAUAAAAAUCAAUAAAAAAGGUUUUGGUAAAACUUUUUCAUGCCAGAUGCUGUUUACAACAAUGAACAUGCCAAUAAAACAUUUGUUCAUUCUGUUGUGUUAUUUUAGUCAUUAAACUUCUGUGGAUGAAGAAUCUGGGUUAAGAAUAGAUUUGUCAUCUUUAAAUAUGACAUUUUGUAAUGUGUAUUGGAUAUCUCAUUUCUAUGAUAAAGGUAUAUUUACAGUAAAGUUCUCAUAAGAGAAAUGAAAAGCUGUGUUAAUAUCUAACUUUGGGGAACCCUGUCAGUAUUUCAGAUCCGAUUUUUACCCUUUUUUUCUUAUAAGAAAGAUAAAAUUAGAAAAUACUGUUAGCAAAUGUGGCUCUGCCAUUUGAAUAUAAUCACCGAGAAUUCCAUGUCUUAAAAGUCUCCUGGAAUCCACAAUGAAAAAAAAAAUCUUUUCUAAGGUAUUUUUCUGGCUAAUUUUUAUUUGAAGAAAGCUAUAGCAUUUAGCGAAAUUUGACUGAAGUAAUGUUCUGAGUUUGCAUUAGUGGGAUUGGUGAUGUUCUCAGAAGAAAAUUGGAAACACUUGUGAUGAAUUGUCUUUCAGAUCACUUAGAUUUUCUGAUGUAAGAGGACAGCUGUUUGGUUCUGAUACAGGCCUGCUUACUUGGGAUGUAGGGUUAGUAAAUGGGGUUUCUGCUUUAAAGGACUGACUUGCUAUCACACAAAAGAGGCAGACUUGUAAACACAAUGGGCUUUGGAGUUUGGUCUGAUUGGGUUUGGUUUAGUAUUCCUAUGAGCGUAAAUGGUAAAAUUCUUCUGAUACCCACUCUUUAGACUGUGCCUUCUGCUCUGUUCUUUGUUUUAUGUUUAACUGCUGUUUCUAAUUGCAGGUGUAUUACAGAUACAAAUAAGAGUAAAGAAAAUAUAUUUCAUUAUAGAAAAGAAAAAAUUAAAAGCUUCUUGCUUUUCAGUGCCUGAUAGAGUGAAAACACAAAGUUGCACUUUAAUAAUUUCAAUAAAAGCUAAUCUGUGUCAGCCUCCCUCUGCUUCAGAGAGUCAGGUGAGCAUCCAUAACCUAACAGGCAGAGCCCUAGCGAUGUGGAUCAAGUUUCCUGAGCCCGGGGGCGGUGGAGCCUCAUGAUCUCUUAUCUUUUGAGGCUGAGGCAGGUCACAUGCAACAAAUUGUGACCCUGCUCCCCACAAGUCAUGCAAAGGUUUUGAAGAGCUUUUACCGUGGGGCAGAUGAACUUGUGUCAACCAUGCACACCCUGUGAGAACCAAGUACCUGUGUUUCUAAGGCGGGCACUCAAGGUGAGGGGUGCAUUCUGGCCAAAGAAACAAAAGCUGUGGUUUCAGGACCAUGCCGUGUGUAGCUGAUCUGUACGGGACGUGUAUGUAAGGAAGAGCAAUCAUGAUAGAUAAGAACAGUGUGUGAAGCAGCCUUCACACUAGAGUGUUUGGUCAUCUCUUAUAAUGUAAGGGAAGGUACUUUAAAAUUCUGGGAAGAUGCGAUGAACUCAUGUCCCAGUCAGAAAAUAAUCCAAUGAAAUAAGCAUUGGUUGCCAGGCCACAGUUAGGAAUUGUAUUGUGAUACAUCUAGAGGCCAAGAGAGCAGGAGAGAGCUACCAACUUACACUGUGGUUUAAGCUAAAUGACCGCACAGCAUCAUAGCAUUGCAGUGUUGUUACUAAAUCUGGAAGUGACCUGUGAAUGUAUGGAAUACAAUAAAGUCUUUUAUUCUGGUUCAUUUGCUAGUACUUCCUUUUUGAUUGGAUACUGUAGUUCUUCCUCUGGAUUUUAUUUUGUUCAGCGUCAAGGCCCUAAUUUUGCAAAUGUAGUCUAAACCACAUUACGUGGACUAGAGGAUACUCUGAAUUAGCAAGUUUUUUGUUUGCUGAAUAAAACUAUUCCAUCUUAACAAUUCUGUGUAAUUUUUGAAAAACAUCAACAUUUUGGUCACUAGUAGUCAAAAUCUUAUAAGGCCAUAUGUCCUGAAAGGCAAAACUCUGUGUAUGUGCGAUUUACCAGGGAGAUAGUAGGACAGUUUUUAUGAGGGUUUCAAAGGAGUUCAUGGCCCAAAUGAAGCUUGUGGCCACCUAGGUUUAGUGUACAUGAAAUUGGAAGAUGCUUCUUGAUUGUAGUUCCCAUGGGGAAGAGGGAGGCUGUGAUCAUUUGGUUAGAUACAGCAUUAAUUGUCACAACUUGACUUUCAGAAACAAGAAUACUGCACAAACUCAAGCAUGCAUUGGAGCAUGUGUUACUAUUUAGAAAAGAGUGCAGCCAUCAGUAGGUCAAGCUAGGAGGGCAAAAGAGAGUUGAGAGGAAUGCUCUGCCCCUUCCCCAUCACAGCACUGCCCCUUUCCACCUCCUCACCAGCUCACCUGUACAAGAGAAUUGAUCUCAACUGAGUGUCAGCUCACCAGGUCAGAAAUUGUUAUUGGACCCUAAAACCUUGCCUCACAGGUGGGCACCAAGCUCCCCUUCCCUCUGCUUUCCAUGUUUCCCACCUGCCCUCUCCCCACCUGUUUUCAGCCUCUUUUAUAAUGCUUAAGUAACCUGCUUGAAGAGUAUAAUUUAUGGAGAUAAAAAUACUCAAUGCUUACAUUUUUUUCAUAACUGUGCCAAUUGUUUUGUCAAAUGCAGUUACCCACUGGGCAGUGGGCUUAUCAAGUGCUCAGUGCAAUCCUGUGACUUUUAAGUCAUUUUGCAUUAUUAAGACAAUCUUAUCUUAAAGUUCAGUGGUUUCAUUCAAAGCUCCCCUGAACCUCCAUAGUGCCUCCAAGAUGUGCUGUCCCUGCCAACUCCUGCACCAGCUUGACUGGUGGUGGAAGAGGCCAGGAAGAGCGGGGGGAAGACAUGUGCUAACCACUUCUUAGCAAUGAGGCUGGUAAGGUUACUGUCCCCUUGUGCCUGGUCACUAGUAACUUUUUUGUAGACAUGAAGGUAGAUGCCCUGCAGGUCCUAUCAGCAAAGGACCCAACUCCUAACAGCAUUGGUGCUCCCUCAUGAAAUUUGACAGUGUCUUGCCAGCCUCCUGCUGGCAGACACUUCUCUGCAGUGAAUACCACUAUCCCAUGCUGCACUAGUCCCUACCAAGUCUUCAACCCUCAAUUUGAUCUUCCAUGAGUGUCUCAAAAAGUUCCCCUCAGAAGUUUCAGCCAAGGGAAUAAAAUCUAACCUCUCCUCCCUCAACGGAGUGUCAGGGAGGGGAAGAAUCUGUUUUCCAAACACCACAAUCUCCCAAAAGGGGAUUUCACCCUCCCUUGGUCAUCUUUAUACAGGGCAAUUGUGCUGCUGCUGCUGAGGUGGCCACUUUCAGCAAGCCCUGUGUGCAGGGGCCUAGCUGCAUUUAGAAACCAAGCAUAGCUAUCAAAAAGUAAUCUCCAAAUAGUUGAAUUGCAUUUCUUGAGUAUCUGGAGAGGAUGUGCAGACCACAGGAAUACCUAAUGCCUUUUUUCUCUUCCUGUCUUUGUCCCUCACACUACAGCAGGCCCCUCCCUUCCCUCUUCAACCUCAUCCUCCCUCCCCACAGGCCCAGAGAACCAGUUGGGCUUUGUUCUCCUGCAGGCUAUGGUUCAUCAUGCAAAUAGCUCCUGUGUCAGAAAUGCUUUUUGGCUUCAAAUAACAGAAAAGCUAACACCAGCUUUAUCAAUAAUAAUAUCGGUGGUUUACUUAAGGUGUCCAGAGAUGGUGGAGAACAGGAUUGGUUUCCUCCUCAAUGUCAAGGACUCAAAGACUCUUUCUGUGGUAGGGCCACAUCCUAAACCCUGUAUCCUGUGAUUAUUUACCUGACAGGGCAAAAGAGAUUUUGCAGAUGCAAUUAAGGUUAAGGACCUUGACGUGGGAAGAUUGUGAUUAUUUACCUGACAGGGCAAAAGAGAUUUUGCAGAUGCAAUUAAGGUUAAGGACCUUGACGUGGGAAGAUUAUUCUGGAUUAUCUAGGUGGGCGCAAUUUGAUCACAUGGGUCCCCAGAAGUGGAGAACCUUUCCCACCUGUAGAAAGCCAGAGAGCUGGCACCUGAGAAGGACAGAACUGUCAUUGCAGGAUUUGAAGAUGAAGGGGCCCAUGAGCCAAGGAAUGCCAGUGACCUAUAGAGGCUAAAAAACAGCAAGGAAAUGGACUCUCCCCAGAGCCUCCAGAGGAAUGCAGCCCUGUUGAUCACAUGAUCACCAGAUGGCUGCCCCAGAGCCAAAUGUCGCUUCCUGAGCACCAUACUCAAAGGCAGGGGAAGUGGAUGGAGGGCAGGAGCUCCAUUCUUGUUUGCCACUCUCCUUUUGUCAAUUGGGAAAAAAUUCCAGAAACUCUGGGAGCCCUCCCCUUACAUUUCCUGGGUCAUGGGGCCAGCCCUAGCUGCUGGAGGGACUGAGAACAGCUGUUGAGCAGUUUACCUGACGGCAUCUGCCAUGGCUUGGCAGGAACUCUGGCUUUGGGAGAGAGCAGCAGCAAGGUAUUCAAGCACCACCUCCACCCAGCCCCUCC